GCGUUUCCUUCCUGUGUGAGGCCGGCUGAGGGCACUUGCUCUUGCUGUUUCUGCCCCUGGGUGAGUAGCUGGUUCCCGUGGGGCCUCAUGGGAUGGUUGUCGUAUCCUUCUGAGGUCCUUUAAGGACCGUCUCGGACCUGGGAACCCCCGGAGGAAAGGUCACCCCGGUCUUCUCCCACGCCCUACCUCAGUGCCGCCCCCAAGCGCCCCGCAGCCCUUAGUAUCUAGAGGAUUAACCUCCAAGGGCGUCCCGGGCCUCGCCUUGGCGUCCGGCCCGGCCUGGGCCCUUAGGGUCUGCUUAGCUCUUCCCCAAGACUCGUGCCAUUCCCGAGGGAAUCUUUGUCGGCAUCCUGGUCACUGUGGGGGUUUGAGGUCGUCCCGGAAGACUUCAGAACCAGGCGAACCUAGACGAAGGCGGCUGGAAUGAACCAGGUUAACAUUCAAGAUGGUACAUGCUGAAGCCUUUUCUCGUCCUUUGAGUCGGAAUGAAGUUGUUGGUUUAAUUUUCCGUUUGACAAUAUUUGGUGCAGUGACAUACUUUACUAUCAAAUGGAUGGUAGAUGCAAUUGAUCCAACCAGAAAGCAAAAAGUAGAAGCUCAGAAACAGGCAGAAAAACUAAUGAAGCAAAUUGGAGUGAAAAAUGUGAAGCUCUCAGAAUAUGAAAUGAGUAUUGCUGCUCAUCUUGUAGACCCUCUUAAUAUGCAUGUUACUUGGAGUGAUAUAGCAGGUUUAGAUGAUGUCAUUACGGAUCUGAAAGACACAGUCAUCUUACCUAUCAAAAAGAAACAUUUGUUUGAGAAUUCCAGGCUUCUGCAGCCUCCAAAAGGUGUUCUUCUCUAUGGGCCUCCAGGCUGUGGUAAAACGUUGAUUGCCAAGGCCACAGCCAAAGAAGCAGGCUGUCGAUUUAUUAACCUUCAGCCUUCGACACUGACCGAUAAGUGGUAUGGAGAAUCUCAGAAAUUGGCUGCUGCUGUCUUCUCCCUUGCCAUAAAGCUACAACCAUCCAUCAUCUUUAUAGAUGAAAUAG